CCUCAGCCUCCCAAAGUGCUGGGAUUACAGGACUGAGCCACUGCGCCCGGCCGCAAACUGUCUUUUCAACGGCAGUUGUCUCCUGAUCUGUUGGCCUCCCUCUACCUGAAUAAAAACAAAAUUCUGGGUACAUUUUUAAACAGCCCCCACCAAACUCCACUCAACAAAACUGUGCAUAGAGUCCCAGAUGGGGUUAAUGUACCACAGAGCCUCUAAGAUGAAUGAGGCCUUACAGUAUACCUGGGCCAACCUCUUUUGUCUGCAGCUAGAAAAUUGAGGCCUGGUGGGGAAGUGACUGUCCUUCUCAGUGGUGGAGUGGGCAGUGCCAGGCCUGGAACCACAAUUCCUGACACCCUGGCCUCUGCCCUUGCCCAUGCUCCUCCUAGGGCAAGCCGGUCCCCCAAGCUCCGCAGCUGGGGGCCCAGCCUCCAGAACGCCCGCUCGCCUCAGGUCUGAGGGUUUUCCUUGUCCUCAGAGACUGGGGAAAUACACGGCCUGGUUCCCCCUACCCACCAGUCCUCUAAGCAAUCCUGGAAAGAUAAGCAGGGCCUUGGUCAUCCGAGGAUGUGAGGCAGGCCCGUCCCCACUCUGAGGGUGUGUCUUUCCUGUCCCAAACUGACCACCUGCCAAGAGGUCACUCCAGGGCUGCCGAUCAAAGAACCCAGCACCUGGUGCCAGAACCCAGGGCAAACUCCUUCCCUCAGACACAAGUCCAGGGGGAGGGAGGGAUGGCUGCCUCUUGGAAGACAAGCCUCUCCCUUAUGUCCUGGGCUGAAGCCACCCUGUCCUGUUAUGUAAUACAAGGAUAUAACACAGAGAGAGAGUUGUCCAGAGGAGAAUGAAAAGGAAGGAUAGGGGCUUUCCUUCCAGUCUGAGCACCUGUCCUGUCCCUCCCUGAACUUGGGCCAGCCUGGACCCUAGCAGAGUCAAUGUCCUGCAGAGGACACAUGCCAUCAGGUGGAGAGAGAGGUCAGGGUCACUCUGCUGGACCUGUCCCAGGAUCACCUUGAGCUCAACAUGUCAUCCUUGUCUACAUUGUGAAGGCCCCUCGGAGAGCCUGGUACCAUACUACUGCACAGCAGGGCGGGGGACCCGAUCCAUGCUCCUGGGCCUGUGACGGGAACGGCAGCGCCAGGCAGUCGCAGGCCUGGGUUCCAGCUUCCACUGCAUAACCUCAGGCAACUCACUCCCUGGGCAUCUGUUUCCUCGUCUGCAAAAUGAAGGUGUUGGAUCAGACGCUCCGGAAGAGAAACAGAUUCCUCAGGGGACAGUCACCUCAGAUGGUCUCCUGCCCCUCUGUGGCUUGUCCAGGGAGCAGCAGAGGCCUGAGACCCUCAAUGUGUCCCUGGACAUGAGCAUGGGAAGAGGCCCUGUGUCCCAAGGCAAGGCACUUCAUUUCUCUGGGCCUCUCCUCCAAACCAUGGUCAUCCACCAUCCUAACUGUCCACCCCACGGCCAGUGGUUCUCAUGGAGACCAAAGGGGUGACCAGCAGAGCCCGCACACGUCAGUGGAGCUUCCCCAGGCACGGGGCUGUGUGCCGGGCAGGGAGAAGCUACAAGCCUGUGAUGUGGAGUAUACCCAGUAGGUUACACAAUCCAGGGCUCCUAUGGAGCAGGCUCUGGGGGCUGUCCGAGCCAACCCCUCUGCUUCCCCUCCCAGGGACCCAGCCCACCCCCUCCUCCCCCAGGGCUGCAAGGAGCCCUGCCAUAGGCCAACAGCACUCCUGACUUCCCCAGAGAGGCUACAUAUGAGGAGGGGCCAGAGCAUCAGCCGCAGAGAGGAAGAGAAGCUGGGAGCACACACAAAAUCAGGCAGCCUCCAAGGACCCCAGAAAAGACCCCUCAGGGCAGCCCUGGCUGCUGUCGGGUCUGACGCCCUCAGUGGCUGUCACAUGGUGGAUGAUUAUCCCCGUGGGCUCAGGAGCUGGCAGCCUGAAUUUGGAUCCGGGCUCUGCCACCUUCCAGCUGCGUGACCUCACCUUGCCGUGCCUCCCUGUCCUUGCCAUACAAUGGGAACGACAGCAGCACCCACUUUAAGGGGUGCUUGUGAGGAGUUGAAUGAGAAACACGCCUGGCACAUAGCGAGCUUGCAACAAGCACUGCUGUUGGGAUUGUCACCCCCUCACUGGAUCCACACGGCUGCAAGGUCCACCCCACUAUGGACCUCGCGUUUCCCAUAUGCAGACAUCGGUGUCAUAGUUAGGCUGGCCACAUGGUUCUGAAGGCCUAGCUCAAACCUGGGAUCCGUAACAUAACAUGGUGAUGUCACCCUCUGCCUCAGUUUCCCCAGCUGCAAAAUGCAGUGAUAAUGAUCACGGAUGUCUGUUAGGGUUGCAGAGUGACUUACAAGAAAUUAUGCAUCAGAAGCACCCUGUCAAGGGCAGGAGUAAGGACUGGAUAAAUGUGAGCUACUAUUAUUGGCUCCUGUCCCACAGGGGGAACCCCAGUUCCCUGCCCCAGGGGUCAUACAGCUAUUUCAUAAAACACCAGGCCUGUUCUCAAAGUUUCUGGGUUGCUCACCGACCAUUCUCUCUGUGACUCCACCAUGGGACCAGUAGGGGAGGGAUGAGCCUCAGCCCUGGAGGGCACCAGGCCCCUUCCCCAGGAGGAAGGGCAGGAGAGGAAGCACCCAGUCCCUCCCCCAGCACAGGCUGGCCAUGCUUCUCCUUAACAGGCCACUGUCACAGCCUCCAGGGUGCAGGGCGAGCCACACUGCCGGAUGGGGCCUUGGGCAGUGCCCACUGCAGGCUCCCAGCGGGUGUCGGCUGCAGAGGCACAGAGCAGGAAAAGGCCCCUCCAAGCUUCUUCCUGGAGACUCAACCCUGGGCUGUCUGGGGACAGUGGGUUCCUUCCCUGUUCCUCAUACUUCUGAGGGCCUGGCGCCAGAGUGGAGACCACAUUCUUUCUUCUGGAAAGCCCCCAAGUCCACACAGCAGGGGAGGAAGGAUGGGUUACGGAAGAGGAGGGGCGAGAGGACAGGCUGAGCCCAGAAAGAACCCUUCCUAAGUGCAGCUUCCUGCCAGGCAGGAGGGUUGCAAGGUCUUAGCACGCACAGUCGUGUCUGUGUCUGCUUGGAGCCCCUUGCCCUCUACCCCUACCACCAGGACCACUGGCCUCGCCUUUUACCACCUUUGCUAAGAGGAGCUCUGGAGACCCCACUCAGGAAAGGGAUAAGUGCCCACAUGCAUAGGGCCCUCACCCUCCACUGGGCACCCCCUCCCUGGUCACUCACCCAUCACCCUGCACCUAUCUGCCCAGCUUAGGGGCCUAGAGUCUCCACUGGGUGUGGCCGAGGCUCAUCCUGGCCUUCUCUGUGAAGGGCACCCCUCUGGCCUCUGGCCUCAAGGCUGGAUGCAGGGACUGGGGCAAAAAGCACUGCGCAUCCUCCACCUGGCCCACACACCCUUAUUCAAGCCAGGUGGCAACCAGCCCAUGGGGAGCCCCAAGCAGCUAUCAAAAGGGGAAGCAGAGCCAUGAUUUUUUAAAAAAAAAAAAAAAGGGACCCAGCAGGUGGGGAAGGUGAGUAGCGGGGAGAAGCGAGGCGGCCUUGCUGCCAGGCAAUCAGGCUACUCUCGGCCUUUCCAGACGGUUUGCCUGUCAUCGGGCACCCCAUAUUUAGCACCAGUGCUUGGGCCCCCACCCCUUGUCUGCCCUCCAGCCCACCCAUUUCCGAGAGCUCAGCCUGGCUCUCCACUGCCCAGAGGAGGCCCUGGGGGCUUUGGAAAGAGCAGAGUGGCCAGCCACUGCCACCCAAGCAGGAAAACCAUGGGGUGGGGUACACUGUGUACAACCAUACCUGGGAAGACCGGCCUCCCAGGCCGGUGCUGGGGAACUAGAGAAGUGAGUGCCAAAUCCCUGCCCUUAGGGAGGGGCAGUGGGGGUGGGUGCACAGCCCUGAGGCGGCACCUGAGCAGGCAGCGUCCAGAGAGAACCUGGGGCCCCGCAGAGUCACGGCAGUCAGUGGACAGAGGCCCAUGAACACCCAAAGACAAAAACAGACCCUGCUUCGGGACGGCAAGCGGGAGAGCAUCGUCAGCACCCUCUUCAUCUCCCCUGGUGACGUGGAGAAUGGCCAGAGCAUCGUGUGUCGUGCCACCAACAAAGCCAUCCCCGGAGGAAAGGAGACGUCGGUCACCAUUGACAUCCAGCACCCUCCACUGGUCAACCUCUCGGUGGAGCCACAGCCAGUGCUGGAGGACAACGUCGUCACUUUCCACUGCUCUGCAAAGGCCAACCCAGCUGUCACCCAGUACAGGUGGGCCAAGCGGGGCCAGAUCAUCAAGGAGGCAUCUGGAGAGGUGUACAGGACCACAGUGGACUACACGUACUUCUCAGAGCCCGUCUCCUGUGAGGUGACCAACGCCCUGGGCAGCACCAACCUCAGCCGCACGGUUGACGUCUACUUUGGGCCCCGGAUGACCACAGAACCCCAAUCCUUGCUCGUGGAUCUGGGCUCUGAUGCCAUCUUCAGCUGCGCCUGGACCGGCAACCCAUCCCUGACCAUCGUCUGGAUGAAGCGGGGCUCCGGAGUGGUCCUGAGCAAUGAGAAGACCCUGACCCUCAAAUCCGUGCGCCAGGAGGACGCGGGCAAGUACGUGUGCCGGGCUGUGGUGCCCCGUGUGGGAGCCGGGGAGAGAGAGGUGACCCUGACCGUCAAUGGACCCCCCAUCAUCUCCAGCACCCAGACCCAGCACGCCCUCCACGGCGAGAAGGGCCAGAUCAAGUGCUUCAUCCGGAGCACGCCGCCGCCGGACCGCAUCGCCUGGUCCUGGAAGGAGAACGUUCUGGAGUCGGGCACAUCGGGGCGCUAUACGGUGGAGACCAUCAGCACCGAGGAGGGCGUCAUCUCCACCCUGACCAUCAGCAACAUCGUGCGGGCCGACUUCCAGACCAUCUACAACUGCACGGCCUGGAACAGCUUCGGCUCCGACACUGAGAUCAUCCGGCUCAAGGAGCAAGGUUCGGAAAUGAAGUCGGGAGCCGGGCUGGAAGCAGAGUCUGUGCCGAUGGCCGUCAUCAUUGGGGUGGCCGUAGGAGCUGGUGUGGCCUUCCUCGUCCUUAUGGCAACCAUCGUGGCGUUCUGCUGUGCCCGUUCCCAGAGAAAUCUCAAAGGUGUUGUGUCAGCCAAAAAUGAUAUCCGAGUGGAAAUUGUCCACAAGGAACCAGCCUCUGGUCGGGAGGGUGAGGAGCACUCCACCAUCAAGCAGCUGAUGAUGGACCGGGGUGAAUUCCAGCAAGACUCAGUCCUGAAACAGCUGGAGGUCCUCAAAGAAGAGGAGAAAGAGUUUCAGAACCUGAAGGACCCCACCAAUGGCUACUACAGCGUCAACACCUUCAAAGAGCACCACUCAACCCCGACCAUCUCCCUCUCCAGCUGCCAGCCCGACCUGCGUCCUGCGGGCAAGCAGCGUGUGCCCACAGGCAUGUCCUUCACCAACAUCUACAGCACCCUGAGCGGCCAGGGCCGCCUCUACGACUACGGGCAGCGGUUUGUGCUGGGCAUGGGCAGCUCGUCCAUCGAGCUUUGUGAGCGGGAGUUCCAGAGAGGCUCCCUCAGCGACAGCAGCUCCUUCCUGGACACGCAGUGUGACAGCAGCGUCAGCAGCAGCGGCAAGCAGGAUGGCUAUGUGCAGUUCGACAAGGCCAGCAAGGCUUCUGCUUCCUCCUCCCACCACUCCCAGUCCUCGUCCCAGAACUCUGACCCCAGUCGACCCCUGCAGCGGCGGAUGCAGACUCACGUCUAAGGAUCACACACCGCGGGUGGGGACGGGCCAGGGAAGAGGUCAGGGCACGUUCUGGUUGUCCAGGGACGAGGGGUACUUUGCAGAGGACACCAGAAUUGGCCACUUCCAGGACAGCCUCCCAGCGCCUCUGCCACUGCCUUCCUUCGAAGCUCUGAUCAAGCACAAAUCUGGGUCCCCAGGUGCUGUGUGCCAGAGGUGGGCGGGUGGGGAGACAGACAGAGGCUGCGGCUGAGUGCGCUGUGCUUAGUGCUGGACACCCGUGUCCCCGGCCCUUUCCUGGAGGCCCCUCUACCACCUGCUCUGCCCACAGGCACAAGUGGCAGCUAUAACUCUGCUUUCAUGAAACUGCGGUCCACUCUCUGGUCUCUCUGUGGGCUCUACCCCUCGCUGACCAGAAGCUCUACCUACCCCUGUGCCUGUGCUCCCAUACAGCCCUGGGGAGAAGGGGAUGACGUCUUCCCAGCACUGAGCUGCCCCAGAAACCCCGGCUCCCCACUGCUGCUCAUAGCCCAUACCCUGGAGGCUGACAAGCCAGAAAUGGCCUUGGCUAAAGGAGCCUCUCUCUCACCAGGCUGGCCGGGAGCCCACCCCCAAUUUGUUUGGUGUUUUGUGUCCAUACUCUUGCAGUUCUGUCCUUGGACUUGAUGCCGCUGAACUCUGCGGUGGGACCGGUCCGGUCAGAGCCUGGUGUACUGGGGGGAGGGAGGGAGGAGGGAGCCUGUGCUGACGGAGCACCUCGCCGGGUGUGCCCCUCCUGGGCUGUGUGACCCCAGCCUCCCCACCCACCUCCUGCUUUGUGUACUCCUCCCCUCCCCCUCAGCACAAUCGGAGUUCAUAUAAGAAGUGCGGGAGCUUCUCUGGUCAGGGUUCUCUGAACACUUAUGGAGAGAGUGCUUCCUGGGAAGUGUGGCGUUUGAAGGGGCUGGAGGGCAGGUCUUUAAGAUGGCGAGACUGCCCUUCUCAGCUGAUAAACACAAGAACGGCGAUCCUGUCUUCAGUAAGGCUCCACGAGAAGAGAGGAAGUAUAUCUACACCUCAACCCUCCUAGUCACCACCUGAAAUAAAUGUUAGGGACACUACUCCAACAUGUUUGUUCUGUUCUUUUGUUCCUACAAAGCCACAGGAAGAACCCAAGAGCUCAUAGAAUGCGUUGGGAACCCAAGGUUCUCUGCCCUCCUUUGAUUCAAUCUUCCUAGACAAUAAAGGCAGUUGAUAGCUCUGA